AUCGCUGGGGGACAGCCUGCAGGCUUCAGGAGGGGACACAAGCAUGGAGCGGCUUUGGGGUCUAUUCCAGAGAGCGCAACAACUGUCCCCAAGAUCCUCUCAGACCGUCUACCAGCGUGUGGAAGGCCCCCGGAAAGGGCACCUGGAGGAGGAAGAGGAAGACGGGGAGGAGGGGGCGGAGACAUUGGCCCACUUCUGCCCCAUGGAGCUGAGGGGCCCUGAGCCCCUGGGCUCUAGACCCAGGCAGCCAAACCUCAUUCCCUGGGCGGCAGCAGGACGGAGGGCUGCCCCCUACCUGGUCCUGACGGCCCUGCUGAUCUUCACUGGGGCCUUCCUACUGGGCUACGUCGCCUUCCGAGGGUCCUGCCAGGCGUGCGGAGACUCUGUGUUGGUGGUCAGUGAGGAUGUCAACUAUGAGCCUGACCUGGAUUUCCACCAGGGCAGACUCUACUGGAGCGACCUCCAGGCCAUGUUCCUGCAGUUCCUGGGGGAGGGGCGCCUGGAGGACACCAUCAGGCAAACCAGCCUUCGGGAACGGGUGGCAGGCUCGGCCGGGAUGGCCGCUCUGACUCAGGACAUUCGCGCGGCGCUCUCCCGCCAGAAGCUGGACCACGUGUGGACCGACACGCACUACGUGGGGCUGCAAUUCCCGGAUCCGGCUCACCCCAACACCCUGCACUGGGUCGAUGAGGCCGGGAAGGUCGGAGAGCAGCUGCCGCUGGAGGACCCUGACGUCUACUGCCCCUACAGCGCCAUCGGCAACGUCACGGGAGAGCUGGUGUACGCCCACUACGGGCGGCCCGAAGACCUGCAGGACCUGCGGGCCAGGGGCGUGGAUCCAGUGGGCCGCCUGCUGCUGGUGCGCGUGGGGGUGAUCAGCUUCGCCCAGAAGGUGACCAAUGCUCAGGACUUCGGGGCUCAAGGAGUGCUCAUAUACCCAGAGCCAGCGGACUUCUCCCAGGACCCACCCAAGCCAAGCCUGUCCAGCCAGCAGGCAGUGUAUGGACAUGUGCACCUGGGAACUGGAGACCCCUACACACCUGGCUUCCCUUCCUUCAAUCAAACCCAGUUCCCUCCAGUUGCAUCAUCAGGCCUUCCCAGCAUCCCAGCCCAGCCCAUCAGUGCAGACAUUGCCUCCCGCCUGCUGAGGAAGCUCAAAGGCCCUGUGGCCCCCCAAGAAUGGCAGGGGAGCCUCCUAGGCUCCCCUUAUCACCUGGGCCCCGGGCCACGACUGCGGCUAGUGGUCAACAAUCACAGGACCUCCACCCCCAUCAACAACAUCUUCGGCUGCAUCGAAGGCCGCUCAGAGCCAGAUCACUACGUUGUCAUCGGGGCCCAGAGGGAUGCAUGGGGCCCAGGAGCAGCUAAAUCCGCUGUGGGGACGGCUAUACUCCUGGAGCUGGUGCGGACCUUUUCCUCCAUGGUGAGCAACGGCUUCCGGCCCCGCAGAAGUCUCCUCUUCAUCAGCUGGGACGGUGGUGACUUUGGAAGCGUGGGCUCCACGGAGUGGCUAGAGGGCUACCUCAGCGUGCUGCACCUCAAAGCCGUAGUGUACGUGAGCCUGGACAACGCAGUGCUGGGGGAUGACAAGUUUCAUGCCAAGACCAGCCCCCUUCUGACAAGUCUCAUUGAGAGUGUCCUGAAGCAGGUGGAUUCUCCCAACCACAGUGGGCAGACUCUCUAUGAACAGGUGGUGUUCACCAAUCCCAGCUGGGAUGCUGAGGUGAUCCGGCCCCUACCCAUGGACAGCAGUGCCUAUUCCUUCACGGCCUUUGUGGGAGUCCCUGCCGUCGAGUUCUCCUUUAUGGAGGACGACCAGGCCUACCCAUUCCUGCACACAAAGGAGGACACUUAUGAGAACCUGCAUAAGGUGCUGCAAGGCCGCCUGCCCGCCGUGGCCCAGGCCGUGGCCCAGCUCGCAGGGCAGCUCCUCAUCCGGCUCAGCCACGAUCGCCUGCUGCCCCUCGACUUCGGCCGCUACGGGGACGUCGUCCUCAGGCACAUCGGGAACCUCAACGAGUUCUCUGGGGACCUCAAGGCCCGCGGGCUGACCCUGCAGUGGGUGUACUCGGCGCGGGGGGACUACAUCCGGGCGGCGGAAAAGCUGCGGCAGGAGAUCUACAGCUCGGAGGAGAGAGACGAGCGACUGACACGCAUGUACAACGUGCGCAUAAUGCGGGUGGAGUUCUACUUCCUUUCCCAGUACGUGUCGCCAGCCGACUCCCCGUUCCGCCACAUCUUCAUGGGCCGUGGAGACCACACGCUGGGCGCCCUGCUGGACCACCUGCGGCUGCUGCGCUCCAACAGCUCCGGGACCCCCGGGGCCACCUCCUCCACUGGCUUCCAGGAGAGCCGUUUCCGGCGUCAGCUAGCCCUGCUCACCUGGACGCUGCAAGGGGCAGCCAAUGCGCUUAGCGGGGAUGUCUGGAACAUUGAUAACAACUUCUGAGGCCCUGGGGAUCCUCACAUCCCCGUCCCCCAGUCAAGAGCUCCUCUGCUCCUCGCUUGAAUGAUUCAGGGUCAGGGAGGUGGCUCAGAGUCCACCUCUCAUUGCUGAUCAAUUUCUCAUUACCCCUACACAUCUCUCCACGGAGCCCAGACCCCAGCACAGAUAUCCACACACCCCAGCCCUGCAGUGUAGCUGACCCUAAUGUGACGGUCAUACUGUCGGUUAAUCAGAGAGUAGCAUCCCUUCAAUCACAGCCCCUUCCCCUUUCUGGGGUCCUCCAUACCUAGAGACCACUCUGGGAGGUUUGCUAGGCCCUGGGACCUGGCCAGCUCUGUUAGUGGGAGAGAUCGCUGGCACCAUAGCCUUAUGGCCAACAGGUGGUCUGUGGUGAAAGGGGCGUGGAGUUUCAAUAUCAAUAAACCACCUGAUAUCAAUAA